GCUGAUUAAAGAACAACGCGCAACCAGCGCCAUACGGCGCUCCUCAGGGUGACUCGGCUCUCUAGCUCUUAAGGGUUAGAAGCGACCCUCGCACGGUCCCCGGUGGGUCACCGCGCGAGGGCGGGGCAGUCCAGGCGACCCCUCGGCCGUCUCCCGUCCUACGGCUGUCAGGGAAGGGCUCCGGUUCCGGUAGGGUCUGCAUUUGGAAAGCCGGGGGCGAUGCAAGACCGCCUUGGCGUCGUCUCCCUCUCAGCCCCGGCUGAGCUGUCGGAUGGUCCCCCUCCCCCGGUUGCAAGCAGUAGGAGACCCGGCCGGCGGCGCCGGCUCGCCGAGGGAGCGCCUCGACCUCCCCGGCAGGCGCCGGCCCCGCGCGCCUCUUCCUGCUCUGCUGCGGCCCGGAGGCUUGUGGGUAACCGGGAGGACGACGUCAGCGCCCGCCGCAUCCCCGGGUGCCCCCCAGCCGCGGGGGACCGCGACGGCUCCGUGACCGUCACGUGCCGGAGGCCGCGGCUGCUCGCGGCCAGACCUUCGCAUCGAGGGACGUGAGGGACAUUUGUCCUAGAGGGCCCAAGAUAAGAACGAGAGGAAGAACCGGGAGGCAACUCUCCGUCAUCCUCUAGCCCCCCGCAUCCUAGGAAACGUAUGGAAAACAAUGGAAGGUUAAGUGUGUGCACAGUGAUCUGGCCCUGCAGGAGUGUGCCGACCAGGUGAUAUUUCCUGGGGCCUGGUGAUAAGGAUUUGGAAGGUUACAGCACAGAGACGUGAACGUAAAAAGGAAACAGAGGCAGCAAGCAAAUGAGGAAACCGAUACUCUGUUCUGAGAAUAAAGCCAUUUUACCGCUAGACGUCAUACUCUGUAGACGUUAUAGUGCUGGAUGUCUUUGGUACUAUUACAAGAAAUUAGAUAUCUCUAUCUUUAAAUAUCACUUAAGGAAAUUAAAUGAUUUCUACAGAUCAGUUAUUUAAAAGGGCACUAAUUAUGAACUAUUUUUUUUAAACGUAACCCGGUUAAUACUAGAUACUGAGAAUUAUCAGUAUUGGCUGGGCGCAGUGGCUCACGCCUGUAAUCCCAGCACUUUGGGAGGCCGAGGCAGGCGGAUCACGAGGUCCGGAAAUCGAGACCAUCCUGGCUAAGACGGUGAAACCCCGUCUCUACUAAAAAUACAAAAAAUUAGCCGGGCGUGGUGGGGGGCGCCUGUAGUCCCAGCUACUCAGGAGGCUGAGGCAGGAGAAUGGCGUGAACCCGGGAAGCGGAGCUUGCAGUGAGCCGAGAUCGCGCCACUGCACUCCAGCCUGGGCGACACAGAGAGGCUAUGUCUCAAAAAAAAAAAAAAAAAUCUCAUUACUAUUAAUCAUUAAAUAUUUUUAAACGUAUGCUUUAAGUAGUACCACAAGUUACAGCUAUCAGUAAAAGCAUACUUUUUAUUUGUGAUAUGACAUUUUAAAACACAGAUGGCCAAAGCGGGCCACCAAGUCUAGCUUAAUUCUAUCUCCAGGAAAGAGGGAUUAAAUUGGUCUUUUUUUUUUUUCUAUGAGCCUUUCUACCUCCAUUCUUCUUUUUCUUCCUCCUGUGUCUUCCUUGCUUUGUUGAUAAACUGUUGCCUUGACCCGGCACCUGGGUUUCUCCCUUGAGGAGAAUCUAGUAAAUUGUCCCCAGGGAUCUUAUAUUAGCCUGUUUCUAAUAGCUAUGCUGACAGCAAGAGUUUAAAAUUGGAGUUAUGUGAAGUAGAUGCAUAGUCUUUUCCUGCAAAACAUUACAAAAUACAGUUAGUAUACUUGAUCUGGUGGCAUAUUUAGGAAAAUGGCCAUUAAAAAUAAUAGUUUACAUUUUCAGUAUCUAACAUCUUCUGAGGUUUAGACGAUGCUUACUGUUCGCCAUAGAAAAUGAACAAGGAGCUCAUUAAGACAGCAAUCUAACACAAUUCUCAGGGCCAGAGUCAUGGAGGAAAAAAUAUUUUUUUAAAAAUUUCUCUUCUGAAGAUUACAUACAGAAUCUUACAUGAUAAAUCUCUUAUCCUGAAAGUCAAAGAAAUUGCCAAGUCUCAUAACUAGGGAAGACGGACAUUACUUUGAACAGAUAUCUCAAUAAGAAGAGUUCUUAGCCCUUCCCUUUUUAGGAUAGGAUUGCUGACAUAUGGCCAUGGUAGAAAACCUAGCUCAUCUUUCAAAUACUGGGCAUGGAAUCGUUCAUCUGGUUUAUGAAUACUUAAUGAUAUUCACUGUGCCUGGUUGUAAGUGAAUACAAUGCAUGAAUAAGAAUAUUUCCCCGUAUAAAAUGUCUCCCAGGGAACUGAAAAUAUUUUUGCAUCCUUUAAGAUCUUUUCCAGAAAAGUACCAGUACAUGGUAGUGCAAUGAUUAAUUUAUGAAAUUAGUGUGAAAACUACAUCUACCUUCUAGAGCUCAAAAUUUGACCACCAGGAAUUUUCAGUGAGGGAAAAGUAAAGAGUCCAAAGCUUUGUAGAUUUUAAUACUGGUAAACAGAACGUGAAGUGAAACCUUUAUGUGCAAAGUUGAACAUCAGACAUGCACAAAGAGACCUCUAGUGGCCAAACUGAAAAGUUUUGCCUAUUUAACAGUGGAUCUAUUUGGUUAUUAGCUGAAAAAUCCUUUGUGGAUUAAAAGCAGUCUGCAUUUUUUACUGACGUUUAAUACCGCCAUCUUCCAUUCUUAAAAAUGUGUAGCCCAGAUGAGUAAAGUCUGUGGUCAGCUCACAUGUCAGGAGACGUAUUCUCCGUGAGAAAGCGAUUCCUUGCUGUAUGGUGGUCGAGUAGAGCCACUAAGAAAAAAAAAAUUUUUUUUUGAGGUGGAAUCUCGCUCUUGUCGCCCAGGCUGGAGUGCAGUGGCGCGAUCUCGACUCACUGCAACCCCUGCCUCCCGGGUUCAAGCGAUUCUCCUGCCUCAGCCUCCAGAGUAGCCGGAACUACAGGCGCACGCCACCAUGCCCGGCUAAUUUUUGUAUUUUUUUUUAGUAGAGACAGGGUUUCACCAUGUUGGCCAAGAUGUUUUCUGUCUCCUGACCUUGUGAUCCGCCCGCCUCGGCCUCCCAAAGUGCUGGGAUCACAGGCGUGAGCCACCGCGCCCAGCCUAAAUAAAAAAAAUUUUUAACUCUUUCUUCUGGAGCCAGAUAAAAUGGAUGGGAAAAGAUAACUGGGGAAUGAGAAUAUUUCUAGAUGUUUCAUUUUCCCAAGAUGGCUCAGUUGGCCAUCCUAGGAACUGAAGUGCCCUCAAACCUGCAGUGUCUGUCAUUUCACAGCUACUAUAACAUACAUUUUAUAUGCUGAGAUUUCUAUACAAAUUAUUAAUCACAAACAACACUUGUUAAGGGACCAUUGAGAAAGCAAAUAUUUUUAGUAGAAUACAGAUUUCCAUAUGAAGAUUUCACAGUAUUCCAGCCUCUGGAGAGGAAGGGAGAGGAAUGCGCUCCUUCCGAUUCCCGCCCUUUCUGCGACACCAUCAAAUCCUCUCAGCGCCCCUCUGGCAGUUCCGGAUUUGCAGGGUCCGAGGGAGAAUACAUCAAAGUGAUGUCAUUCAUGACUCCGAAAUGGUUACCAUGGCGACUAUCAGACAUAUUAAGCUGUCAGGGAAAGAGCCUGUUUAAUCCAGUCUUCAAUCACGGGUUUCCUCGGGCGUUAGCCACUGCCUGCGGAGUGUGGACUGGCAGAAAAACGUCACCUUCGGGCCCCCCAGCACCAACGCGCCUUAAACCAAGCCCCACAAAGAAGUCACUUCGGCGAUGUAAACGCGACUUUGCGGCUUCCUGGGCUGCUAAGGUCCCUAUGUUAACUACUUGAGACAAAAAUAAAUAUGGCCUUCUACAGUUAUAAUUCAGUUCUGGCUAUUGCUCGAACAAGAUUCCCUAGCCAUUUUGUCCAUCCUACCUGCUCUUCUUAUUCCCCAUCAUGUGCAUUUCUUCACUUGCCAGAUUCCCAUUUAAAUAAGACAUGUAUGAAGAACUAUGAGAGCAAGAAGUACUCGGAUCCUAGUCAGCCAGGCAAUACAGUACUUCACCCAGGAACUAGACUAAUACAAAAGCUACACACAUCCACUUGCUGGCUGCAAGAAGUUCCUGGCAAACCUCAGCUGGAGCAAGCCACAAAACAUCCACAGGUGACAAGCCCUCAGGCCACAAAAGAAACUGGCAUGGAGAUUAAAGAAGGCAAACAAUCUUAUAGACAAAAAAUCAUGGAUGAACUAAAAUAUUAUUACAAUGGAUUCUACUUACUUUGGAUUGACGCCAAAGUUGCUGCCAGAAUGGUUUGGAGGCUGUUGCAUGGACAGGUCCUGACCAGACGAGAGAGACGAAGGCUGUUGAGAACUUGUGUUGAUUUCUUCCGCCUGGUUCCAUUUAUGGUGUUCUUAAUUGUACCCUUCAUGGAAUUCUUAUUACCAGUGUUUCUGAAACUCUUCCCAGAGAUGUUGCCAUCAACUUUUGAAAGUGAAUCCAAAAAGGAAGAAAAACAGAAAAAGAAAAUGGCUGUAAAGUUGGAACUAGCAAAAUUUCUUCAAGAAACCAUGACAGAAAUGGCAAGGAGGAACAGAGCCAAGAUGGGCGAUGCCUCUACACAGCUCUCAUCCUACGUGAAGCAGGUCCAGACAGGCCACAAGCCCAGCACAAAGGAGAUAGUUCGCUUCUCCAAACUAUUUGAGGACCAGCUGGCCCUGGAACACUUAGAUCGCCCUCAGCUGGUUGCCCUUUGCAAACUGCUGGAAUUGCAGACAUUUGGAACCAACAACCUGCUCCGCUUUCAGCUCCUGAUGAAACUGAAGUCUAUAAAAGCAGAUGAUGAAAUAAUUGCCAAGGAAGGGGUGACAGCAUUGAGUGUAUCAGAACUACAGGCUGCCUGUAGGGCCCGAGGGAUGAGAUCACUGGGUCUCACGGAGGAACAACUGCGACAACAGCUCACGGAGUGGCAGGACCUCCACCUGAAGGAGAACGUCCCUCCUUCCCUUUUGCUCCUGUCCCGCACCUUCUACCUGAUAGAUGUGAAGCCCAAGCCGAUUGAGAUACCACUCAGUGGGGAGGCUCCAAAGACUGAUAUUCUUGUGGAAUUACCUACUUUCACUGAAUCUAAAGAGAACAUGGUGGAUCUUGCACCUCAACUGAAGGGAACUAAGGAUGAAGACUUUAUACAGCCGCCACCAGUUACAUCAUCACCCAUAACACCAUCAACACCUAUUUCAUUACCUAAAGGACCCAUCACUUCUUCUGAAGAACCUACACUCCAGGCCAAAUCACAAAUGACGGCCCAGAACAGCAAGGCUAGUUCAAAAGGAGCAUAAAGGACUACUUGAGGAUGGAGCUCACUCUCUUCAGCUUCCGGCCCUCAACAGUGGCAUCUGUAAAGGACCUCCCAGAUAAGACUGUCUGGCUUCAGAGAGCGGAUCAGCUGUUUAGCCCGUGGGGCAGUCCUUUGAGGCCUGGUAACCAUUCCAGGUGAUGUGGGUAGUGAGACCAAGUUCAGACCACUUAGAAAAAUAUAAUUGCAAAGUCCCAUUUCCUCUGUACCAUUGUCACCCCACUCAACUUUGUAUAAAGCCCACCCCCCAUCAUGUUGUUUUUUUAGUUUCAUGUGUACGUCCCUUCAGAGAGGAAAUUUUUUGCACAAUGGAAUCAGCUUGGCACCUUAGAUACCUGUCUCCUAUGGCUUGGAAUUCUGAGUAAGAACUUGGAAGUUCCAAAAACCAUUUUAGGAGCACCUGAUUAACUUUCUGAAUGAUCCACCAGUAGGAUCAGCACCCUGGAAACAAAGUACCUUAUGAGAUGGGAUGGAUAUACUCCCCAGUAAGAUCUUUCUGGAUAUAAUGAAGCUUCCUGGAGAAACAGACUGGCAAUCAGAAAGAUUUGGCUGCUUCCGACACCUCCAUCUUGGGCCUGCAGAGGCUGCAGCAAUCUGUGAGGCAGCCGCAAUCUGCGAGGCAGCCACUCUUCUAGCACAUAUGGCUUUCAUUAGCCACCAUUUUGCUAGGAAGCAUAAUUAAGGGUUUAAGCCUUAACCAUGUUUGUGUUGGGUGUGUGUGUUUCUGGCCAGUUUGUCUUUCACAAAUAAGACUAUUAGUCAUAGGGAUUGUGAAAGUCUGAUAUAAUCCCUGUGCUACCCAGCAACAAGUAUUACAUUAGGAUAUUUAUGCUUGGUGUUUUCAGUAUUAAUAAUAUGAAAUAAUAGAUAGACUGCCAUGCAGCUGACCAAGGGCUUUCUUCCCCUGGGGAGUGGUUAGAAGGCCAAAGGUAUUUCAGCCUGUAGGUGAUAAAAUUAGAUUUCUUUACUUGCUGUGGUUAGACAGCAGUCAGUUAAAACAAGUAAAACUCCACUGUCCUGUCUGGGAUCACCUAAAUGAGGAAUGUCACCAGCACUUCACAGCAAGAAUAUGCAUUCUACAAUGCUUUCUAAAUUUGUGCUCCAUCAGAGAAGCCCCACCAUGUCCCACUAAUGAAGCCCAGUUCUUUGGGAAUGAUGAAUCCCUACUGUGCACAUACAGCAAUCAUGGAUCCUGCCUAUCGAGGUGAUUCACAAUACACUUUCCCAUUUCAAAAA